GAGUCUGGGGACGCAGGCAAGCACAAAGACAAGGGGGAUGGAGCUUCUACACAGGGCCCCAGCGCUGUCGCUGUGGCUGCUGCUGCCGCUACGGCUUAGUGCACCAGACGCUGCAUUUCAGGUGCUCCUACAAAAGAGGCCACUCCUGGAACGCCGGGAGCUCAGACGCUGCCCUUUGCUCGCGAGCCAAGUCAGCCAAGGUUAACCUUCGCGGAACCCGGCGAGGAGCGCAAGCCUGGCCUUCCCCAAACACAGAUCCGAGCUUUUCACCCUCUACCCUCCCCUCAGCCUGGCCUUUUCUUCCGCCCUCACAGCCACCGCGACCCAACGCUGAGGAAAGACCCCGACUUGUGGUGUCCUUCCCCUUGCCCAAACUGGCCACGAAAGGACAUAUAGCGAGAGAGAAAGAGGAUUUUCUGCCGUCUCUUGGCAAAAAUGGCAAAUAAUGAUGCUGUUCUGAAGAGACUGGAGCAGAAGGGUGCAGAGGCAGAUCAAAUCAUUGAAUAUCUUAAGCAGCAAGUUUCUCUACUUAAGGAGAAAGCAAUUUUGCAGGCAACUUUGAGGGAAGAGAAGAAACUUCGAGUUGAAAAUGCUAAACUGAAGAAAGAAAUUGAAGAACUGAAACAAGAGCUAAUUCAGGCAGAAAUUCAAAAUGGAGUGAAGCAAAUACCAUUUCCAUCUGGUACUCCACUGCACGCUAAUUCUAUGGUUUCUGAAAAUGUGAUACAGUCUACAGCAGUAACAACCGUAUCUUCUGGUACCAAAGAACAGAUAAAAGGAGGAACAGGAGACGAAAAGAAAGCGAAAGAGAAAAUUGAAAAGAAAGGAGAGAAGAAGGAGAAAAAACAGCAAUCAAUAGCUGGAAGUGCCGACUCUAAGCCAAUAGAUGUUUCCCGUCUGGAUCUUCGAAUUGGUUGCAUCAUAACUGCUAGAAAACACCCUGAUGCAGAUUCUUUGUAUGUGGAAGAAGUAGAUGUCGGAGAAAUAGCCCCAAGGACAGUUGUCAGUGGCCUGGUGAAUCAUGUUCCUCUUGAACAGAUGCAAAAUCGGAUGGUGAUUUUACUUUGUAACCUGAAACCUGCAAAGAUGAGGGGAGUAUUAUCUCAAGCAAUGGUCAUGUGUGCUAGUUCACCAGAGAAAAUUGAAAUCUUGGCUCCUCCAAAUGGGUCUGUUCCUGGAGACAGAAUUACUUUUGAUGCUUUCCCAGGAGAGCCUGACAAGGAGCUGAAUCCUAAGAAGAAGAUUUGGGAGCAGAUCCAGCCUGAUCUUCACACUAAUGAUGAGUGUGUGGCUACAUACAAAGGAGUUCCCUUUGAGGUGAAAGGGAAGGGAGUAUGUAGGGCUCAAACCAUGAGCAACAGUGGAAUCAAAUAAAAUGCUUCCACUACCAAAAGACAUUAGAGAAAACCUUAAAAGUAAUAAAGAGAAAUAUAUUUGUCACUUAUACCUAAAAUAUGAGUGGCUCAUUUUUGCAUUACUCUCUUCUAGACUUGACUAGUCAUUUACUUGGUAUAUAUUGUUUUCAUUGAUUGGGGAAACACUAGAUUUUUACCUCGGUUUUUGAUCAUUUAUAAUGGAGAGAGGAAGUUGCCUAUGUUUUGUAAUAAUUUAUUUUUUAGCAGGAAUAUUGAUUAGCAGCUUUUUUUUCUUUAUACACAUAGAUAACUAACUAGAUUAAUGUUUAGUUUCUUAUUUGUAGGCACAGGAUGCAUGAAAUUUCAAGCUCUGGGAUUUUUUGUAUAUUGUGUAUCUGUAUCAAAAAUAUCCUCUCCUUUUCAAAAAUGACAGGUUGGAAAAUGUUUGUCAGACUUAUUAACUGGUCAUAUUAUAAUAAUACUGAUAAUGACCAACUGCUCAUUCUGAAAGCCAAACAUAAAAGCUAGGAGAAGUGGCAUCUGAACAUUUUUGCUUUGCUGCCAGAGUAACCCUGACUAAUAAUACAAUAACAGCAAUUUUUUUAAAAAACUGAGAUUUCCUACUGGCUUGAAGUUUUUCUAUUUAGCAAAAUAAUUAGUAAUAAGUUUUGACUAGGUCUAAAGAAUGAACACAUUGUAAACAGUUGCCACAGUAGUUUCUAAUAAAUUGAUCAUAAAAGCAGCUAUCCUUUUUUUUUUUAAUUCUAGCUUCUUUUUAAAGAUUAUUUGGGUACCUAAUAAAGGAUAAUUUAUAUCUUAUUACAGACUGAUAUUUUGCUUUUUCAUGUGUCAUCAUACUGUCAGUAUAUUAAAAGAAAUUACAGCCUAAAACUUAACAUAUACCAUACAUAUAUAUUAAGGUGUCAAAUAGCUAUUCUCACUCAUCUUACAAAUAUUGUAAGAGCAAUAAAAAUUAAUUGAGGAAUUAUAAGCCUACAGGUCAUCAGCCUUGAGGUGAUUACUGAUGAUUUGGGCUUACACACAUGUCAGCAAGAUAGGGAGUGUGGAUAGGGGAGGGCUGGUAGCUAACAAGGGGCCUCACAGAGAAAUAUUAGUGACUUUAACCAGGUUUCAGAAUCUGGGCCUUACCUUUACAGGUUCAACAAAAGAAUGGCAUCAAUAGAGGCAGAAGUAUAGACAUUGUUUUAAAAAUACACACAUGCACACACACACAAAACAUUUUAGCAUUAUAGCUGUCUGAAUCCUUCAAUAAGAAGGAGAGGCACACACAAAUACACACACUCACACAAAACUCAACAACCAUAAAACAACCCUGCAUGUUAUAAAAGGCAGAAUUAAAUUUUAUUUAUUUAAAUCCAUGGAACUCUGGUAGGCCAGGAUAUAUUAUAGUACCAUUAUCAAUGUGAUAUUCUGAAAAUAUGAACUGAGCGUCAUUAACAAUUGUUGGUACCUAAACACAAAAUGAAUUUCAAAAGUUACUUUGUUCUCAAGAUAUGUCAUUCUUUUGGGAAUAAAUACUUCUGGUGACAAAGUCUUUUGUGAGUUUUUUGCUCUAAUUUUUCUCAAUUAUAUUAAAUUUCUUUAAUAUAAUUUAAAUAAUAUUUCAACUACCUAGGUAGUUGAAAUUUUCCCAACUAAAUGUUGAAAUACUGUACCCCAGAUCAAAUUAUCUAAUGUUUUGUUAGUGAAACCUAAACUGAUGAUUAAAUCGUUCAUCAAACCUAGAGAUAAUAAAAACUAUUGGUCUUUUGUUAAAAGCCCA